AUAGAGGAAGAGCUUUGGACGUAGGGAUGUCAAACUGGUCUAGAAUGUAAUGAAAACCCAAGAAGGUGCCCCAGUAAGAAAGAGGAAAUCAAUCUAACAAUGGGAUGCAGCAGCAAGAAUACUGAGACAGGAAAGAAAAUAUUUUAAAAAAAUGAAUUAUUCAUUCACUUUCUAGUGGAUACAGAAAAAACUGCAGAAGACCCAGAGGAUAUCAGGGCAGGCUAAAAGUUUGAUAUCUUACACCUGUGGAAAAGCCUUAAGCUCUGUUUUAACUGAGAGCAGGUGGGGUGACUUCAUGACUACCAUUAAGAAAAUAUAACCUGUUGGGAAACUGUUUCUGCCUUGAUGAUGUUGUACAGACAAGAGAUAAACAGUGAGGAAUAUGCUUAGAUGUAUUGGGAAAGACAUGGGUCUGUGGCAUUGUCACAAGGGUACACGAAUACUGAGAGUGAAUGCUGAAGGAAUGAUCCCCAUUGGUGGUGACCCUCAGGUGAAAGUAGGGUGCCUGUGUUUCAGCAAAGCCUGGGCAAUUGGAAUGCAGAGCUCCUAAGAUUCCAUGACACCCCCACCUUCUAAUUCUGUUAUUGCAACUGCAGACGGUUACCUGGCACGCUGGCCACAUUCUGCCUCACUCUUAUCAGAGUCUGAGCUACUGGCAGUGCUUUCAGCUCUGAGUUGAGGCACCUCGAACCUUGUUUUUGUGGUGAAGGAUCCUAAAGUGCUGUGGGGAGUGAUCACAUUUUUCACAACAUCCCUGACUCCACCUCUUCUGCCACAAACGUCAGCAUGGUGGUAUCAGCCGGCCCUUGGUCCAGUGAGAAGGCAGAGAUGAACAUUCUAGAAAUCAACGAGACAUUGCGCCCCCAGCUGGCAGAGAAGAAACAGCAGUUCAGAAACCUCAAAGAGAAAUGUUUUCUAACUCAACUGGCCGGCUUCCUGGCCAACCGACAGAAGAAAUACAAGUAUGAAGAGUGUAAAGACCUCAUAAAAUUUAUGCUGAGGAAUGAGCGACAGUUCAAGGAGGAGAAGCUUGCAGAGCAGCUGAAGCAAGCUGAGGAGCUCAGGCAAUAUAAAGUCCUGUUUCACUCUCAGGAACGAGAGCUGACCCAGUUAAGGGAGAAGUUACGGGAAGGGAGAGAUGCCUCCCGCUCAUUGAAUGAGCAUCUCCAGGCCCUCCUCACUCCGGAUGAGCCGGACAAGUCCCAGGGGCAGGACCUCCAAGAACAGCUGGCUGAGGGGUGUAGACUGGCACAGCACCUUGUCCAAAAGCUCAGCCCAGAAAAUGACAACGAUGACGAUGAAGAUGUUCAAGUUGAGGUGGCUGAGAAAGUGCAGAAAUCGUCUGCCCCCAGGGAGAUGCAGAAGGCUGAAGAAAAGGAAGUCCCUGAGGACUCACUGGAGGAAUGUGCCAUCACUUAUUCAAAUAGCCAUGGCCCUUAUGACUCCAACCAGCCACAUAGGAAAACCAAAAUCACAUUUGAGGAAGACAAAGUCGACUCAACUCUCAUUGGCUCAUCCUCUCAUGUUGAAUGGGAGGAUGCUGUACACAUUAUUCCAGAAAAUGAAAGUGAUGAUGAGGAAGAGGAAGAAAAAGGGCCAGUGUCUCCCAGGAAUCUGCAGGAGUCUGAAGAGGAGGAAGUCCCCCAGGAGUCCUGGGAUGAAGGUUAUUCGACUCUCUCAAUUCCUCCUGAAAUGUUGGCCUCGUACCAGUCUUACAGCAGCACAUUUCACUCAUUAGAGGAACAGCAAGUCUGCAUGGCUGUUGACAUAGGCAGACAUCGCUGGGAUCAAGUGAAAAAGGAGGACCAAGAGGCAACAGGUCCCAGGCUCAGCAGGGAGCUGCUGGAUGAGAAAGGGCCUGAAGUCUUGCAGGACUCACUGGAUAGAUGUUAUUCAACUCCUUCAGGUUGUCUUGAACUGACUGACUCAUGCCAGCCCUACAGAAGUGCCUUUUACGUAUUGGAGCAACAGCGUGUUGGCUUGGCUAUUGACAUGGAUGAAAUUGAAAAGUACCAAGAAGUGGAAGAAGACCAAGACCCAUCAUGCCCCAGGCUCAGCAGGGAGCUGCUGGAUGAGAAAGAGCCUGAAGUCUUGCAGGACUCACUGGAUAGAUGUUAUUCGAUUCCUUCAGGUUAUCUUGAACUGCCUGACUUAGGCCAGCCCUACAGCAGUGCUGUUUACUCAUUGGAGGAACAGUACCUUGGCUUGGCUCUUGACGUGGACAGAAUUAAAAAGGACCAAGAAGAGGAAGAAGACCAAGACCCACCAUGCCCCAGGCUCAGCAGGGAGCUGGUGGAGGUAGUAGAGCCUGAAGUCUUGCAGGACUCACUGGAUAGAUGUUAUUCAACUCCUUCCAGUUGUCUUGAACAGCCUGACUCCUGCCAGCCCUAUGGAAGUUCCUUUUAUGCAUUGGAGGAAAAACAUGUUGGCUUUUCUCUUGACGUGGGAGAAAUUGAAAAGAAGGGGAAGGGGAAGAAAAGAAGGGGAAGAAGAUCAAAGAAGGAAAGAAGAAGGGGAAGAAAAGAAGGGGAAGAAGAUCAAAACCCACCAUGCCCCAGGCUCAGCAGGGAGCUGCUGGAUGAGAAAGGGCCUGAAGUCUUGCAGGACUCACUGGAUAGAUGUUAUUCAACUCCUUCAGGUUGUCUUGAACUGACUGACUCAUGCCAGCCCUACAGAAGUGCCUUUUACAUAUUGGAGCAACAGUGUGUUGGCUUGGCUGUUGACAUGGAUGAAAUUGAAAAGUACCAAGAAGUGGAAGAAGACCAAGACCCAUCAUGCCCCAGGCUCAGCAGGGAGCUGCUGGAUGAGAAAGAGCCUGAAGUCUUGCAGGACUCACUGGAUAGAUGUUAUUCGAUUCCUUCAGGUUAUCUUGAACUGCCUGACUUAGGCCAGCCCUACAGCAGUGCUGUUUACUCAUUGGAGGAACAGUACCUUGGCUUGGCUCUUGACGUGGACAGAAUUAAAAAGGACCAAGAAGAGGAAGAAGACCAAGACCCACCAUGCCCCAGGCUCAGCAGGGAGCUGGUGGAGGUAGUAGAGCCUGAAGUCUUGCAGGACUCACUGGAUAGAUGUUAUUCAACUCCUUCCAGUUGUCUUGAACAGCCUGACUCCUGCCAGCCCUAUGGAAGUUCCUUUUAUGCAUUGGAGGAAAAACAUGUUGGCUUUUCUCUUGACGUGGGAGAAAUUGAAAAGAAGGGGAAGGGGAAGAAAAGAAGGGGAAGAAGAUCAAAGAAGGAAAGAAGAAGGGGAAGAAAAGAAGGGGAAGAAGAUCAAAACCCACCAUGCCCCAGGCUCAGCAGGGAGCUGCUGGAUGAGAAAGGGCCUGAAGUCUUGCAGGACUCACUGGAUAGAUGUUAUUCAACUCCUUCAGGUUGUCUUGAACUGACUGACUCAUGCCAGCCCUACAGAAGUGCCUUUUACAUAUUGGAGCAACAGUGUGUUGGCUUGGCUAUUGACAUGGAUGAAAUUGAAAAGUACCAAGAAGUGGAAGAAGACCAAGACCCAUCAUGCCCCAGGCUCAGCAGGGAGCUGCUGGAUGAGAAAGAGCCUGAAGUCUUGCAGGACUCACUGGAUAGAUGUUAUUCGAUUCCUUCAGGUUAUCUUGAACUGCCUGACUUAGGCCAGCCCUACAGCAGUGCUGUUUACUCAUUGGAGGAACAGUACCUUGGCUUGGCUCUUGACGUGGACAGAAUUAAAAAGGACCAAGAAGAGGAAGAAGACCAAGACCCACCAUGCCCCAGGCUCAGCAGGGAGCUGGUGGAGGUAGUAGAGCCUGAAGUCUUGCAGGACUCACUGGAUAGAUGUUAUUCAACUCCUUCCAGUUGUCUUGAACAGCCUGACUCCUGCCAGCCCUAUGGAAGUUCCUUUUAUGCAUUGGAGGAAAAACAUGUUGGCUUUUCUCUUGACGUGGGAGAAAUUGAAAAGAAGGGGAAGGGGAAGAAAAGAAGGGGAAGAAGAUCAAAGAAGGAAAGAAGAAGGGGAAGAAAAGAAGGGGAAGAAGAUCAAAACCCACCAUGCCCCAGGCUCAGCAGGGAGCUGCUGGAUGAGAAAGGGCCUGAAGUCUUGCAGGACUCACUGGAUAGAUGUUAUUCAACUCCUUCAGGUUGUCUUGAACUGACUGACUCAUGCCAGCCCUACAGAAGUGCCUUUUACAUAUUGGAGCAACAGUGUGUUGGCUUGGCUGUUGACAUGGAUGAAAUUGAAAAGUACCAAGAAGUGGAAGAAGACCAAGACCCAUCAUGCCCCAGGCUCAGCAGGGAGCUGCUGGAUGAGAAAGAGCCUGAAGUCUUGCAGGACUCACUGGAUAGAUGUUAUUCGAUUCCUUCAGGUUAUCUUGAACUGCCUGACUUAGGCCAGCCCUACAGCAGUGCUGUUUACUCAUUGGAGGAACAGUACCUUGGCUUGGCUCUUGACGUGGACAGAAUUAAAAAGGACCAAGAAGAGGAAGAAGACCAAGACCCACCAUGCCCCAGGCUCAGCAGGGAGCUGGUGGAGGUAGUAGAGCCUGAAGUCUUGCAGGACUCACUGGAUAGAUGUUAUUCAACUCCUUCCAGUUGUCUUGAACAGCCUGACUCCUGCCAGCCCUAUGGAAGUUCCUUUUAUGCAUUGGAGGAAAAACAUGUUGGCUUUUCUCUUGACGUGGGAGAAAUUGAAAAGAAGGGGAAGGGGAAGAAAAGAAGGGGAAGAAGAUCAAAGAAGGAAAGAAGAAGGGGAAGAAAAGAAGGGGAAGAAGAUCAAAACCCACCAUGCCCCAGGCUCAGCAGGGAGCUGCUGGAUGAGAAAGGGCCUGAAGUCUUGCAGGACUCACUGGAUAGAUGUUAUUCAACUCCUUCAGGUUGUCUUGAACUGACUGACUCAUGCCAGCCCUACAGAAGUGCCUUUUACAUAUUGGAGCAACAGUGUGUUGGCUUGGCUGUUGACAUGGAUGAAAUUGAAAAGUACCAAGAAGUGGAAGAAGACCAAGACCCAUCAUGCCCCAGGCUCAGCAGGGAGCUGCUGGAUGAGAAAGAGCCUGAAGUCUUGCAGGACUCACUGGAUAGAUGUUAUUCGAUUCCUUCAGGUUAUCUUGAACUGCCUGACUUAGGCCAGCCCUACAGCAGUGCUGUUUACUCAUUGGAGGAACAGUACCUUGGCUUGGCUCUUGACGUGGACAGAAUUAAAAAGGACCAAGAAGAGGAAGAAGACCAAGACCCACCAUGCCCCAGGCUCAGCAGGGAGCUGGUGGAGGUAGUAGAGCCUGAAGUCUUGCAGGACUCACUGGAUAGAUGUUAUUCAACUCCUUCCAGUUGUCUUGAACAGCCUGACUCCUGCCAGCCCUAUGGAAGUUCCUUUUAUGCAUUGGAGGAAAAACAUGUUGGCUUUUCUCUUGACGUGGGAGAAAUUGAAAAGAAGGGGAAGGGGAAGAAAAGAAGGGGAAGAAGAUCAAAGAAGGAAAGAAGAAGGGGAAGAAAAGAAGGGGAAGAAGAUCAAAACCCACCAUGCCCCAGGCUCAGCAGGGAGCUGCUGGAUGAGAAAGGGCCUGAAGUCUUGCAGGACUCACUGGAUAGAUGUUAUUCAACUCCUUCAGGUUGUCUUGAACUGACUGACUCAUGCCAGCCCUACAGAAGUGCCUUUUACAUAUUGGAGCAACAGUGUGUUGGCUUGGCUGUUGACAUGGAUGAAAUUGAAAAGUACCAAGAAGUGGAAGAAGACCAAGACCCAUCAUGCCCCAGGCUCAGCAGGGAGCUGCUGGAUGAGAAAGAGCCUGAAGUCUUGCAGGACUCACUGGAUAGAUGUUAUUCGAUUCCUUCAGGUUAUCUUGAACUGCCUGACUUAGGCCAGCCCUACAGCAGUGCUGUUUACUCAUUGGAGGAACAGUACCUUGGCUUGGCUCUUGACGUGGACAGAAUUAAAAAGGACCAAGAAGAGGAAGAAGACCAAGACCCACCAUGCCCCAGGCUCAGCAGGGAGCUGCUGGAGGUAGUAGAGCCUGAAGUCUUGCAGGACUCACUGGAUAGAUGUUAUUCAACUCCUUCCAGUUGUCUUGAACAGCCUGACUCCUGCCAGCCCUAUGGAAGUUCCUUUUAUGCAUUGGAGGAAAAACAUGUUGGCUUUUCUCUUGACGUGGGAGAAAUUGAAAAGAAGGGGAAGGGGAAGAAAAGAAGGGGAAGAAGAUCAAAGAAGGAAAGAAGAAGGGGAAGAAAAGAAGGGGAAGAAGAUCAAAACCCACCAUGCCCCAGGCUCAGCAGGGAGCUGCUGGAUGAGAAAGGGCCUGAAGUCUUGCAGGACUCACUGGAUAGAUGUUAUUCAACUCCUUCAGGUUGUCUUGAACUGACUGACUCAUGCCAGCCCUACAGAAGUGCCUUUUACAUAUUGGAGCAACAGUGUGUUGGCUUGGCUGUUGACAUGGAUGAAAUUGAAAAGUACCAAGAAGUGGAAGAAGACCAAGACCCAUCAUGCCCCAGGCUCAGCAGGGAGCUGCUGGAUGAGAAAGAGCCUGAAGUCUUGCAGGACUCACUGGAUAGAUGUUAUUCGACUCCUUCAGGUUAUCUUGAACUGCCUGACUUAGGCCAGCCCUACAGCAGUGCUGUUUACUCAUUGGAGGAACAGUACCUUGGCUUGGCUCUUGACGUGGACAGAAUUAAAAAGGACCAAGAAGAGGAAGAAGACCAAGGCCCACCAUGCCCCAGGCUCAGCAGGGAGCUGCUGGAGGUAGUAGAGCCUGAAGUCUUGCAGGACUCACUGGAUAGAUGUUAUUCAACUCCUUCCAGUUGUCUUGAACAGCCUGACUCCUGCCAGCCCUAUGGAAGUUCCUUUUAUGCAUUGGAGGAAAAACAUGUUGGCUUUUCUCUUGACGUGGGAGAAAUUGAAAAGAAGGGGAAGGGGAAGAAAAGAAGGGGAAGAAGAUCAAAGAAGGAAAGAAGAAGGGGAAGAAAAGAAGGGGAAGAAGAUCAAAACCCACCAUGCCCCAGGCUCAGCAGGGAGCUGCUGGAUGAGAAAGGGCCUGAAGUCUUGCAGGACUCACUGGAUAGAUGUUAUUCAACUCCUUCAGGUUGUCUUGAACUGACUGACUCAUGCCAGCCCUACAGAAGUGCCUUUUACAUAUUGGAGCAACAGUGUGUUGGCUUGGCUGUUGACAUGGAUGAAAUUGAAAAGUACCAAGAAGUGGAAGAAGACCAAGACCCAUCAUGCCCCAGGCUCAGCAGGGAGCUGCUGGAUGAGAAAGAGCCUGAAGUCUUGCAGGACUCACUGGAUAGAUGUUAUUCGACUCCUUCAGGUUAUCUUGAACUGCCUGACUUAGGCCAGCCCUACAGCAGUGCUGUUUACUCAUUGGAGGAACAGUACCUUGGCUUGGCUCUUGACGUGGACAGAAUUAAAAAGGACCAAGAAGAGGAAGAAGACCAAGGCCCACCAUGCCCCAGGCUCAGCAGGGAGCUGCUGGAGGUAGUAGAGCCUGAAGUCUUGCAGGACUCACUGGAUAGAUGUUAUUCAACUCCUUCCAGUUGUCUUGAACAGCCUGACUCCUGCCAGCCCUAUGGAAGUUCCUUUUAUGCAUUGGAGGAAAAACAUGUUGGCUUUUCUCUUGACGUGGGAGAAAUUGAAAAGAAGGGGAAGGGGAAGAAAAGAAGGGGAAGAAGAUCAAAGAAGGAAAGAAGAAGGGGAAGAAAAGAAGGGGAAGAAGAUCAAAACCCACCAUGCCCCAGGCUCAGCAGGGAGCUGCUGGAUGAGAAAGGGCCUGAAGUCUUGCAGGACUCACUGGAUAGAUGUUAUUCAACUCCUUCAGGUUGUCUUGAACUGACUGACUCAUGCCAGCCCUACAGAAGUGCCUUUUACAUAUUGGAGCAACAGUGUGUUGGCUUGGCUGUUGACAUGGAUGAAAUUGAAAAGUACCAAGAAGUGGAAGAAGACCAAGACCCAUCAUGCCCCAGGCUCAGCAGGGAGCUGCUGGAUGAGAAAGAGCCUGAAGUCUUGCAGGACUCACUGGAUAGAUGUUAUUCGACUCCUUCAGGUUAUCUUGAACUGCCUGACUUAGGCCAGCCCUACAGCAGUGCUGUUUACUCAUUGGAGGAACAGUACCUUGGCUUGGCUCUUGACGUGGACAGAAUUAAAAAGGACCAAGAAGAGGAAGAAGACCAAGGCCCACCAUGCCCCAGGCUCAGCAGGGAGCUGCUGGAGGUAGUAGAGCCUGAAGUCUUGCAGGACUCACUGGAUAGAUGUUAUUCAACUCCUUCCAGUUGUCUUGAACAGCCUGACUCCUGCCAGCCCUAUGGAAGUUCCUUUUAUGCAUUGGAGGAAAAACAUGUUGGCUUUUCUCUUGACGUGGGAGAAAUUGAAAAGAAGGGGAAGGGGAAGAAAAGAAGGGGAAGAAGAUCAAAGAAGGAAAGAAGAAGGGGAAGAAAAGAAGGGGAAGAAGAUCAAAACCCACCAUGCCCCAGGCUCAGCAGGGAGCUGCUGGAUGAGAAAGGGCCUGAAGUCUUGCAGGACUCACUGGAUAGAUGUUAUUCAACUCCUUCAGGUUGUCUUGAACUGACUGACUCAUGCCAGCCCUACAGAAGUGCCUUUUACAUAUUGGAGCAACAGUGUGUUGGCUUGGCUGUUGACAUGGAUGAAAUUGAAAAGUACCAAGAAGUGGAAGAAGACCAAGACCCAUCAUGCCCCAGGCUCAGCAGGGAGCUGCUGGAUGAGAAAGAGCCUGAAGUCUUGCAGGACUCACUGGAUAGAUGUUAUUCGACUCCUUCAGGUUAUCUUGAACUGCCUGACUUAGGCCAGCCCUACAGCAGUGCUGUUUACUCAUUGGAGGAACAGUACCUUGGCUUGGCUCUUGACGUGGACAGAAUUAAAAAGGACCAAGAAGAGGAAGAAGACCAAGGCCCACCAUGCCCCAGGCUCAGCAGGGAGCUGCUGGAGGUAGUAGAGCCUGAAGUCUUGCAGGACUCACUGGAUAGAUGUUAUUCAACUCCUUCCAGUUGUCUUGAACAGCCUGACUCCUGCCAGCCCUAUGGAAGUUCCUUUUAUGCAUUGGAGGAAAAACAUGUUGGCUUUUCUCUUGACGUGGGAGAAAUUGAAAAGAAGGGGAAGGGGAAGAAAAGAAGGGGAAGAAGAUCAAAGAAGGAAAGAAGAAGGGGAAGAAAAGAAGGGGAAGAAGAUCAAAACCCACCAUGCCCCAGGCUCAGCAGGGAGCUGCUGGAUGAGAAAGGGCCUGAAGUCUUGCAGGACUCACUGGAUAGAUGUUAUUCAACUCCUUCAGGUUGUCUUGAACUGACUGACUCAUGCCAGCCCUACAGAAGUGCCUUUUACAUAUUGGAGCAACAGUGUGUUGGCUUGGCUGUUGACAUGGAUGAAAUUGAAAAGUACCAAGAAGUGGAAGAAGACCAAGACCCAUCAUGCCCCAGGCUCAGCAGGGAGCUGCUGGAUGAGAAAGAGCCUGAAGUCUUGCAGGACUCACUGGAUAGAUGUUAUUCGACUCCUUCAGGUUAUCUUGAACUGCCUGACUUAGGCCAGCCCUACAGCAGUGCUGUUUACUCAUUGGAGGAACAGUACCUUGGCUUGGCUCUUGACGUGGACAGAAUUAAAAAGGACCAAGAAGAGGAAGAAGACCAAGGCCCACCAUGCCCCAGGCUCAGCAGGGAGCUGCUGGAGGUAGUAGAGCCUGAAGUCUUGCAGGACUCACUGGAUAGAUGUUAUUCAACUCCUUCCAGUUGUCUUGAACAGCCUGACUCCUGCCAGCCCUAUGGAAGUUCCUUUUAUGCAUUGGAGGAAAAACAUGUUGGCUUUUCUCUUGACGUGGGAGAAAUUGAAAAGAAGGGGAAGGGGAAGAAAAGAAGGGGAAGAAGAUCAAAGAAGGAAAGAAGAAGGGGAAGAAAAGAAGGGGAAGAAGAUCAAAACCCACCAUGCCCCAGGCUCAGCAGGGAGCUGCUGGAUGAGAAAGGGCCUGAAGUCUUGCAGGACUCACUGGAUAGAUGUUAUUCAACUCCUUCAGGUUGUCUUGAACUGACUGACUCAUGCCAGCCCUACAGAAGUGCCUUUUACAUAUUGGAGCAACAGUGUGUUGGCUUGGCUGUUGACAUGGAUGAAAUUGAAAAGUACCAAGAAGUGGAAGAAGACCAAGACCCAUCAUGCCCCAGGCUCAGCAGGGAGCUGCUGGCUGAGAAAGAGCCUGAAGUCUUGCAGGACCCACUGGAUAGAUGUUAUUCGACUCCUUCAGGUUAUCUUGAACUGCCUGACUUAGGCCAGCCCUACAGCAGUGCUGUUUACUCAUUGGAGGAACAGUACCUUGGCUUGGCUCUUGACGUGGACAGAAUUAAAAAGGACCAAGAAGAGGAAGAAGACCAAGGCCCACCAUGCCCCAGGCUCAGCAGGGAGCUGCUGGAGGUAGUAGAGCCUGAAGUCUUGCAGGACUCACUGGAUAGAUGUUAUUCAACUCCUUCCAGUUGUCUUGAACAGCCUGACUCCUGCCAGCCCUAUGGAAGUUCCUUUUAUGCAUUGGAGGAAAAACAUGUUGGCUUUUCUCUUGACGUGGGAGAAAUUGAAAAGAAGGGGAAGGGGAAGAAAAGAAGGGGAAGAAGAUCAAAGAAGGAAAGAAGAAGGGGAAGAAAAGAAGGGGAAGAAGAUCAAAACCCACCAUGCCCCAGGCUCAGCAGGGAGCUGCUGGAUGAGAAAGGGCCUGAAGUCUUGCAGGACUCACUGGAUAGAUGUUAUUCAACUCCUUCAGGUUGUCUUGAACUGACUGACUCAUGCCAGCCCUACAGAAGUGCCUUUUACAUAUUGGAGCAACAGUGUGUUGGCUUGGCUGUUGACAUGGAUGAAAUUGAAAAGUACCAAGAAGUGGAAGAAGACCAAGACCCAUCAUGCCCCAGGCUCAGCAGGGAGCUGCUGGCUGAGAAAGAGCCUGAAGUCUUGCAGGACCCACUGGAUAGAUGUUAUUCGACUCCUUCAGGUUAUCUUGAACUGCCUGACUUAGGCCAGCCCUACAGCAGUGCUGUUUACUCAUUGGAGGAACAGUACCUUGGCUUGGCUCUUGACGUGGACAGAAUUAAAAAGGACCAAGAAGAGGAAGAAGACCAAGGCCCACCAUGCCCCAGGCUCAGCAGGGAGCUGCUGGAGGUAGUAGAGCCUGAAGUCUUGCAGGACUCACUGGAUAGAUGUUAUUCAACUCCUUCCAGUUGUCUUGAACAGCCUGACUCCUGCCAGCCCUAUGGAAGUUCCUUUUAUGCAUUGGAGGAAAAACAUGUUGGCUUUUCUCUUGACGUGGGAGAAAUUGAAAAGAAGGGGAAGGGGAAGAAAAGAAGGGGAAGAAGAUCAAAGAAGGAAAGAAGAAGGGGAAGAAAAGAAGGGGAAGAAGAUCAAAACCCACCAUGCCCCAGGCUCAGCAGGGAGCUGCUGGAUGAGAAAGGGCCUGAAGUCUUGCAGGACUCACUGGAUAGAUGUUAUUCAACUCCUUCAGGUUGUCUUGAACUGACUGACUCAUGCCAGCCCUACAGAAGUGCCUUUUACAUAUUGGAGCAACAGUGUGUUGGCUUGGCUGUUGACAUGGAUGAAAUUGAAAAGUACCAAGAAGUGGAAGAAGACCAAGACCCAUCAUGCCCCAGGCUCAGCAGGGAGCUGCUGGCUGAGAAAGAGCCUGAAGUCUUGCAGGACCCACUGGAUAGAUGUUAUUCGACUCCUUCAGGUUAUCUUGAACUGCCUGACUUAGGCCAGCCCUACAGCAGUGCUGUUUACUCAUUGGAGGAACAGUACCUUGGCUUGGCUCUUGACGUGGACAGAAUUAAAAAGGACCAAGAAGAGGAAGAAGACCAAGGCCCACCAUGCCCCAGGCUCAGCAGGGAGCUGCUGGAGGUAGUAGAGCCUGAAGUCUUGCAGGACUCACUGGAUAGAUGUUAUUCAACUCCUUCCAGUUGUCUUGAACAGCCUGACUCCUGCCAGCCCUAUGGAAGUUCCUUUUAUGCAUUGGAGGAAAAACAUGUUGGCUUUUCUCUUGACGUGGGAGAAAUUGAAAAGAAGGGGAAGGGGAAGAAAAGAAGGGGAAGAAGAUCAAAGAAGGAAAGAAGAAGGGGAAGAAAAGAAGGGGAAGAAGAUCAAAACCCACCAUGCCCCAGGCUCAACAGCGUGCUGAUGGAAGUGGAAGAGCCUGAAGUCUUACAGGACUCACUGGAUGGAUGUUAUUCGACUCCGUCAAUGUACUUUGAACUACCUGACUCAUUCCAGCACUACAGAAGUGUGUUUUACUCAUUUGAGGAAGAGCAUAUCAGCUUCGCCCUUUACUUGGACAAUAGGUUUUUUACUUUGACGGUGACAAGUCUCCAUCUGGUGUUCCAGAUGUUAGUCAUAUUCCCACAAUAGGCAGCCCUUACUAAGCCGAGAGAUGUCAUUCCUGCAGGCAGGACCUAUAGGCACGUGAAGAUUUGAAUGAAACUACAGUUCCAUUUGGAAGCCCAGACAUAGGAUGGGUCAGUGGGCAUGGCUCUUUUCCUAUUCUCAAACCAUGCCAGUGGCAACCUGUGCUCAGUCUGAAGACAAUGGACCCACGUUAGGUGUGACACGUUCACAUAACUGUGCAGCACAUGCCGGGAGUGAUCAGUCGGACAUUUUAAUUUGAACCACGUAUCUUUGGGUAGCUACAAAAUUCCUCAGGGAUUUCAUUUUGCAGGCAUGUCUCUGAGCUUCUAUACCUGCUCAAGGUCAGUGUCAUCUUUGUGUUUAGCUCAUCCAAAGGUGUUACCCUGGUUUCAAUGAACCUAACCUCAUUCUUUGUGUCUUCAGUGUUGGCUUGUUUUAGCUGAUCCAUCUGUAACACAGGAGGGAUCCUUGGCUGAGGAUUGUAUUUCAGAACCACCAACUGCUCUUUACAAUUGUUAACCCGCUAGGCUCCUUUGGUUAGAGAAGCCACAGUCCUUCAGCCUCCAAUUGGUGUCAGUACUUAGGAAGACCACAGCUAGAUGGACAAACAGCAUUGGGAGGCCUUAGCCCUGCUCCUCUCAAUUCCAUCCUGUAGAGAACAGGAGUCAGGAGCCGCUGGCAGGAGACAGCAUGUCACCCAGGACUCUGCCGGUGCAGAAUAUGAACAAUGCCAUGUUCUUGCAGAAAACGCUUAGCCUGAGUUUCAUAGGAGGUAAUCACCAGACAACUGCAGAAUGUAGAACACUGAGCAGGACAACUGACCUGUCUCCUUCACAUAGUCCAUAUCACCACAAAUCACACAACAAAAAGGAGAAGAUAUAUUUUGGGUUCAAAAAAAGUAAAAAGAUAAUGUAGCUGCAUUUCUUUAGUUAUUUUGAACCCCAAAUAUUUCCUCAUCUUUUUGUUGUUGUCAUGGAUGGUGGUGACAUGGACUUGUUUAUAGAGGACAGGUCAGCUCUCUGGCUCAAUGAUCUACAUUCUGAAGUUGUCUGAAAAUGUCUUCAUGAUUAAAUUCAGCCUAAACGUUUUGCCGGGAACACUGCAGAGACAAUGCUGUGAGUUUCCAACCUCAGCCCAUCUGCGGGCAGAGAAGGUCUAGUUUGUCCAUCACCAUUAUGAUAUCAGGACUGGUUACUUGGUUAAGGAGGGGUCUAGGAGAUCUGUCCCUUUUAGAGACACCUUACUUAUAAUGAAGUACUUGGGAAAGCGGUUUUCAAGAGUAUAAAUAUCCUGUAUUCUAAUGAUCAUCCUCUAAACAUUUUAUCAUUUAUUAAUCCUCCCUGCCUGUGUCUAUUAUUAUAUUCAUAUCUCUACGCUGCAAAAUUUGGGUCUCAAUUUUUACUGUGCCUUUGUUUUUACUAGUGUCUGCUGUUGCAAAAAGAAGAAAACAUUCUCUGCCUGAGUUUUAAUUUUUGUCCAAAGUUAAUUUUAAUCUAUACAAUUAAAACCUUUUGCCUAUCACUCUGGACUUUUGGAUUGUUUUUUACAUUCAGUGUUAUAAUAUUUGAUUAUGCUGAUUGGUUUUGGUGGGUACUGAUGUGAAUUAAUAAAAACAUUUCAUUUCCA